AUGCAGAACCAGUCUUCAACAAAUCAUCCUGGAGCUAGCAUUGCACUCUCGAGACCCUGUCUUAAUAAGGACUUCUGGGAUCACGCUGAGCCGCAGUAUAUUGCAGCCCAGCAGAAGGCAGCUUUGCAGCAUGCUCAUGCACAUUCAUUUGGAUACUUCAUAACUCAAGACUCUGCAUUUGGGAACCUGAUUCUUCCUGUUUUACCUCGCCUUGACCCAGAAUGAAGAAAAUAUUUGUGAUGGAAAAGAGACUUUGUAAUAUCAAAUGCCAAAGCUACUGUCAUUCAGUGCUAGAUGAACUGUGACUUUCAAAAUUUUGGUGAACUUUGAUAUUUUUUGUUUGUUAAAGGAAUGUGUAAGUGAAAGCAGAAAGAAGGGUAAUCAGGAUGAUGAGAGCUGUGGAGGCUGUAUCGUCCAAGGAAUUGAUUAUGUACCGUAACUGUAACUUUUUUGUAAUGCUGUUUAACAGUAAUCAGACUCUGAACUGGAUGGUCACAAAAACAUUCCCCAACCCCUAGCAAGUUUGACUGAAUAUAUCAUGUCCACAGUAGAUUUCCAAGAAUCAUUUAUAGUACUUAACUUUAAAGAAACAAGAGUACUUUUAAAAAAUGAACCAAUAAGCUUAAAUCUGUUACAUCCAUAUUUGCUGUUUAUAGGAUUGGUGUCAGUGUACCUUUUGAGUUUACAGUCAACAUGUAUCAUCCUAAAAUAUUAUUUCUGAACUCAUAACUACUUCCCCCUUUCUCACUUUAAAACAAACCCCAAGAAUAAAUUACUAACCAGUCUUAACCAUCUUCUAUAAACAUAUUCUUCUAUAAACAUCUUCUAUAAACCAUCUUCUAUAAACAUCAUUAUAAAUGAUGUGACUAAAUGCAAUUAAAAAUAAUAGAAAAAAAAGGAAAGUGAGAAUAGGAGAUUGUAAUAUCCAUUUUAACUGAGUGAACUUUUCAGAAGAUAUAAAAUGAAAUUACAACAUUUAAAAGGAUUUUCAAAUUUUAAAUUUUUUUCUAUGUACUGCUUUAUAGACUAAGAAGGGGACAGCACAAAUAUUAUAAAUAUUUCAAGGAUAUUAUAUAAAGCAGUAAAAUUAUUGAACAUUAUAUUAGUUUGCUAGGGCUGCUAUAACAAAGUACCACAAGCUAGGUGGCUUAAACGUUAGAAAUUUGUUGUCUCAUUUCUGGAGGUUAGAAGUCUGAAGUCAAGGUAUCUCCAAAUACAGUCACGUCUGAGCAUGGUGGCUCAUGCCUGUAAUCCUAGCACUUUGGAAGGCUGAGGCAGGAGGAUUGCUUGAGCCCAGGAGUUCAAGACCAGCCUGGGCAACAUAGUGAGACCUAAUCUGUACUAAAAAUCAGAAAAAUUAGCUAGACAUGGUACCAUGCACCUGUAGUCCCCGCUACUUGAACGCUGAGGUGGGAGGAUUGCUUGAGCCUGGGAGUUUGAGGCUGCAGUGACCUAUGAUCCUGCCACUGCACUACAGCCUGGAUAACAGAGUGAAACUGUGUCUCAAAACAAAACACACAUAGUCAUGUUCUGAGGUACUACGCACAGUGUGGGAGCAGGUGGGGGGCAAAAUUUAACCCAUAAAAAAGUCAUCCAAGUUUUUUACUACCUGAUUUUACUGCCUAAUGUUCUCUCUUCUAUAGAUAAUAUAUAUAUGAGAUUUCUUUAGAGAAAUAAAACAUCAGUAGAUUUCUUAAAGCAUUGAUAAUGAUCUCUGCAGGUAUUUUGCUAUAGGAAAAAUAAAAAUUGGAAUUGCUUUAUUUAUGAAUUA